ACUUCCGGGUCGGACGGCGCUAGCUGCAGCAUCGGAGUGUGGCAGUGCUGGGCUGGCCGGCGGGCUGGGCUGCGGCCCGCGCGCGGCCGGCGAUGCAGGGGGGCAACUCCGGGGUCCGCAAGCGCGAAGAGGAGGGCGACGGGGCUGGGGCUGUGGCUGCGCCGCCGGCCAUCGACUUUCCCGCCGAGGGCCCGGACCCCGAAUAUGACGAAUCUGAUGUUCCAGCAGAAAUCCAGGUGUUAAAAGAACCCCUACAACAGCCAACCUUCCCUUUUGCAGUUGCAAACCAACUCUUGCUGGUUUCUUUGCUGGAGCACUUGAGCCACGUGCAUGAACCAAACCCACUUCGUUCAAGACAGGUGUUUAAGCUACUUUGCCAGACGUUUAUCAAAAUGGGGCUGCUGUCUUCUUUCACUUGUAGUGACGAGUUUAGCUCAUUGAGACUACAUCACAACAGAGCUAUUACUCACUUAAUGAGGUCUGCUAAAGAGAGAGUUCGUCAGGAUCCUUGUGAGGAUAUUUCUCGUAUCCAGAAAAUCAGAUCAAGGGAAGUAGCCUUGGAAGCACAAACUUCACGUUACUUAAAUGAAUUUGAAGAACUUGCCAUCUUAGGAAAAGGUGGAUACGGAAGAGUAUACAAGGUCAGGAAUAAAUUAGAUGGUCAGUAUUAUGCAAUAAAAAAAAUCCUGAUUAAGGGUGCAACUAAAACAGUUUGCAUGAAGGUCCUACGGGAAGUGAAGGUGCUGGCAGGUCUUCAGCACCCCAAUAUUGUUGGCUAUCACACCGCGUGGAUAGAACAUGUUCAUGUGAUUCAGCCACGAGCAGACAGAGCUGCCAUUGAGUUGCCAUCUCUGGAAGUGCUCUCCGACCAGGAAGAGGACAGAGAGCAAUGUGGUGUUAAAAAUGAUGAAAGUAGCAGCUCAUCCAUUAUCUUUGCUGAGCCCACCCCAGAAAAAGAAAAACGCUUUGGAGAAUCUGACACUGAAAAUCAGAAUAACAAGUCGGUGAAGUACACCACCAAUUUAGUCAUAAGAGAAUCUGGUGAACUUGAGUCGACCCUGGAGCUCCAGGAAAAUGGCUUGGCUGGUUUGUCUGCCAGUUCAAUUGUGGAACAGCAGCUGCCACUCAGGCGUAAUUCCCACCUAGAGGAGAGUUUCACAUCCACCGAAGAAUCUUCCGAAGAAAAUGUCAACUUUUUGGGUCAGACAGAGGCACAGUACCACCUGAUGCUGCACAUCCAGAUGCAGCUGUGUGAGCUCUCGCUGUGGGAUUGGAUAGUCGAGAGAAACAAGCGGGGCCGGGAGUAUGUGGACGAGUCUGCCUGUCCUUAUGUUAUGGCCAAUGUUGCAACAAAAAUUUUUCAAGAAUUGGUAGAAGGUGUGUUUUACAUACAUAACAUGGGAAUUGUGCACCGAGAUCUGAAGCCAAGAAAUAUUUUUCUUCAUGGCCCUGAUCAGCAAGUAAAAAUAGGAGACUUUGGUCUGGCCUGCACAGACAUCCUACAGAAGAACACAGACUGGACCAACAGAAACGGGAAGAGAACACCAACACAUACGUCCAGAGUGGGUACUUGUCUGUACGCUUCACCCGAACAGUUGGAAGGAUCUGAGUAUGAUGCCAAGUCAGAUAUGUACAGCUUGGGUGUGGUCCUGCUAGAGCUCUUUCAGCCGUUUGGAACAGAAAUGGAGCGAGCAGAAGUUCUAACAGGUUUAAGAACUGGUCAGUUGCCGGAAUCCCUCCGUAAAAGGUGUCCAGUGCAAGCCAAGUAUAUCCAGCACUUAACGAGAAGGAACUCAUCGCAGAGACCAUCUGCCAUUCAGCUGCUGCAGAGUGAACUUUUCCAAAAUUCUGGAAAUGUUAACCUCACCCUACAGAUGAAGAUAAUAGAGCAAGAAAAAGAAAUUGCAGAACUAAAGAAGCAGCUAAACCUCCUUUCUCAAGACAAAGGGGUGAGGGAUGACGGAAAGGAUGGGGGCGUGGGAUGAAAGUGGACUUAACUUUUAAGGUAGUUAACUGGAAUGUAAAUUUUUAAUCUUUAUUAGGGUAUAGUUGGUACAAUGCUUCGUUGUAUUUAGUAAGCCUUUACAAGACUUGUUAAAGAUGUCAGAGUGCCCCAAGCUGCCGUUCCUUCCCUUCCUGCCCCACAAGCUCCUUUUCCUGAAUUUCCUACCUAAAUAUUAACCAUAUGCCUAGUCUCUGAAACUAAAAACUUGGACCUCAUCCUCAAUUAUUUUCUCCUUUCAACUCUGUUGACCCUCUGUCUGGUCUUCCUCUAGAAGGUACCGCAGAAAUUGAUGUGUGCUCCCUGCCCUCGUCACUGCCCAAGCCCGGGCCUGCACAUACUCACUGGACUGUUCCAGUUUUGACAGCUGCCAGUCUUCCUGCCCCUUUCACACUGCAGCUGAAGUUCAUUACCUGAAGGACGCCUCAUCAUUUCAUUCCUUGGCUCCAAACCUUCUGCUGCCUCUAAGAUAAAAGCUCAACUUCUUAACAGUGUACAGUGUGCAACUUCCAACCUUUUUAUCUGUUCUCUCCACCUUCAGUUUAGCGUCAUUCCAAAACCACACCCUUGCAAAGCUUUGUACUCCGCACCCCAGAUGAUCUCCAGGCAGCUCAGAUCUCUUUCCUGCCUUUGCCCUGCACUGUUCCCCGGUACUUCCUCCUUUAUUGUAGCACUCAGCUCCCCAGCCAAUCUGUACAUCCCUCAGAGGCAGCGAUCUGAUGAAUUGGUUUUUGAAUCCCAGAAAGGGUCUGCCAUGGAGUUGGCAGUCAUCACGGUAGAUGGCGUAUGAUUUUGCUGAAUUUUAAAUAAAAUGAAAACCAUAAAUUACAUGAUGCUUUUAUUGACACUUGACAACUGGCCUAAAUAAAAAGACUCUGACUCUAAUACAAGUCCCCUUACUGAUAAUAGGCAUGAAAGAGCACCAUUCUUAAAAUCUAAACCCUUUAAAAUCAGUUACGGCAAUUCACUUAAGGAGCUUGAGGGCCGUGUUAAAAGGAGCCAGGUUUUCACAAGACCUCAUCCACCUCUGCACAUUGGCUGGCACUGUCACACUGCAGCCUCCGAUCUGCUGGAGUACAGACCACAGCACCACGUCUGCUACGGUGAGUUCAUUCCCAGCGAGCCAAGGGCUCUUCCCAAGAGCAGAGUUCAUGGAGCGGAAAACAGCGGCUUUUUCUUUACUGCUUCCCUCUUUUAACUGAAAAAUCGCAAUAUCUACCCAGCUAUCUAUAAGGGUUGCGUUGACAGCAUUAUGCUUCUGGCCAAACAGAGAGAACAAGAAACGUGCAAUGUUCCCUUCGCCUUCGAUGGGGCACAUCGUCUGGAUGCUGAAUUUCAUCUGCGUCUUCGGCACUGAAAAGAAAAAACACGCCAGGUAGCAUCACCAGAGCAGCCCUGAGGGAAGUACUCGCACAGUGGGGAAGGGGACAGUCACCAAACACCACAGACUGAUGACAUGGGAAAGGGUGUUUUCAAGAAGAACAUCACAUUUUCAGUCUGUCUCUAAGAUGCUUACUACUGAAAAGGGUUUAAGUGCAAACUAUGUUAAAAAAGUAACCAAAGAGUCAUUCCUGGUAUUUGAUUAUGACACUUCUGAAGCUAGAAGGGACCUCAGACCACCUGCUCCAAUCCCUGCUGCCUAAGGUUUUGGGGGCUGAGGGCUGGAAACCCAGGAGCUGCAUCUCCCAGGCUCUUGGCCUCAUAAUCGCCUUCUGUGAGACUGAGGGCAAUUAAGAUAUGAAUGACAUGAACUCGCUUAUCUCCAUAUCAACAUAAACCAGAAGAGGCAUACAUCUGUGGGAUAGUCAAUACAUAACAUCCUAUCUUUAUAUGGCCAUAUGAGAAGAUAACUUCAGUGUCCCUAUGAUGGUAAGUUCUUGAAUGUGAGGGCAAGAUGGCUGUGAUAGCCAUGACUCCCCGCUUUGCCUGGUUGGACAGAACCCCCUUCCCCAAAUGCUCACAGUCCCCCCCUUGAGCUGUGUCUCACUCAGAGACCCUAAAUUUUGCAGACGAACAAGGGCAUCUUUGCGUUGCUUCAUCUCUGCUCCUCCUCUAGAACUAUCCCACAGGCUUUCUAGACUUAGAAUAUCUGACCUGAUGCAAAUCGCUAUGUGGCCAGUAUGCCACAGAAUGUCCUAAACCCUUGCUGCCUCUUAUCAAAACCAUGUUGCACAUCUCAUCAUAUAGUACAGCUAACCCUUGAACAGUGGGGGGGUUAGGGACACUGACCCCCGACUGCUGUGCAGUCGAAAAUCCACAUAAAACUUCUGACUCCUUCAAAACUUAAGCACUAAUAGCCUACUAUUCAUGGGAAGCCUUACCCAUCACAGUUGAUUAACACGUUUUGUAUGGUCUGUAUAUUAUAUGCUAUAUUCUUACAAUAAACUUGAGAAAAUGUUAAGAAAAUAA